GGGCUGUAAGCGCCGGUCGCGGCUGUGUCGGUCGCCGCUGCUCCCGCUCCUGCUGGGAGAGGUUUCAGGAGUCAGUGACCUUCAAGGAUGUGUCCAUAGAUUUCUCUUGGGAAGAGUGGAUUCAAGCAGAUUCUGCUCAGAGGAUGACCGUGUAUGGGGAGGUGAUGCUGGAGAACUACAGGAACCCGGUCUCACUGGGAAAUCACCUUUCCAAACCCAAUGGGACUUCCCAGCUGGAACGAGAACUGAGUCUGAUGCAAAAAGAACCGCCUGAGGGUGGCUUUCGAGAUUUUCUUGGAUAUUGCUGUCAGAUUAAUCUGACAUUUAGUCCUCUCAUUAUCCUGUCCCAGUCAAGGGGAGAAAGUAUUGACUGAGUGCUGUGCUCAGCUCUUCCACAGCCAGCAUCUCACUUACUUGACACAAAACAUCUAUAGACUGGGAGACAAGACUUGAAACCAAAGAGCCAACUCCGAAGCCGGGUAUUACUGAAGAUUUAUGCCAUGGGGUAACAAUGGAAAGGGAAGGUAUCUGGCAUUCUACUCUAGGGGAAACCUGGGAACCUAAUAAUUGGUUAGAGGGACAACAGGAUAGUCAUCUGAGCCAAGUGGGAGUUACCCAUAAGGAAACCUUCACUGAGAUGAGAGUAUGUGGAGGUAAUGAAUUUGAAAGAUGUUCCAGUCAGGAUUCAAUCCUUGAUACACAGCAAAGCAUUCCUAUGGUAAAAAGGCCCCAUAACUGUAAUUCACAUGGAGAAGAUGCCACACAAAAUUCUGAGUUAAUUAAAACUCAAAGAAUGUUUGUAGGAAAGAAGAUCUAUGAAUGUAAUCAGUGCAGCAAAACCUUCAGUCAGAGCUCAUCCCUUCUUAAGCACCAGAGGAUUCAUACUGGGGAGAAACCCUAUAAGUGUAAUGUAUGUGGGAAACACUUCAUUGAACGAUCCUCCCUUACUGUACAUCAAAGAAUUCAUACUGGAGAGAAACCCUAUAAAUGUAAUGAAUGUGGGAAAGCCUUUAGUCAGAGCAUGAAUCUUACUGUCCAUCAACGAACUCACACCGGAGAGAAACCCUAUCAGUGUAAAGAGUGUGGCAAAGCCUUCCAUAAGAAUUCAUCUCUUAUUCAGCAUGAAAGGAUUCAUACUGGAGAGAAACCCUACAAAUGUAAUGAAUGUGGUAAAGCUUUUACCCAAAGCAUGAAUUUGACAGUUCAUCAGAGAACUCAUACAGGAGAAAAACCCUAUGAAUGUAAUGAAUGUGGAAAAGCCUUCAGUCAAAGCAUGCAUCUUAUUGUACAUCAGAGAAGCCAUACUGGAGAAAAACCCUAUGAGUGUAGUCAAUGUGGAAAAGCCUUUAGUAAGAGCUCAACUCUUACCCUACAUCAGCGAAAUCACACUGGAGAAAAACCUUACAAAUGUAACAAAUGCGGGAAAUCCUUUAGCCAAAGUACAUAUCUUAUAGAACAUCAGAGACUUCAUUCUGGAGUAAAACCUUUUGAAUGUAACGAGUGUGGAAAAGCUUUCAGUAAGAAUUCAUCUCUAACUCAACAUCGGAGAAUUCACACUGGAGAGAAACCUUAUGAGUGUAUGGUGUGUGGAAAACAUUUCACUGGACGAUCAUCCCUUACCGUGCAUCAGGUCAUUCACACUGGAGAGAAACCUUAUGAGUGCAAUGAAUGUGGAAAGGCAUUCAGCCAGAGUGCUUACCUUAUUGAACAUCAAAGAAUUCAUACUGGUGAGAAACCCUAUGAAUGUGAUCAGUGUGGAAAAGCCUUCAUUAAGAAUUCAUCCCUUACAGUGCAUCAGAGAACUCAUACAGGAGAGAAACCCUAUCAGUGUAAUGAAUGCGGAAAAGCCUUCAGCCGGAGUACAAACCUUACACGACAUCAAAGAACUCAUACGUGAGGAAUGUUUUCACUGGCCCUUACCUCAUGAUUAACUCUUCAGUAAUAAUCAUAUGAGACAUACAAUGUAGAAACCUAAUAAAUGUAAUGAUUGUGGGAAUCUUUCAGUUGAAGUACAAUAUGUCAUAUCAGAUAAUACCACUGCAGAGAAUCCAUCUAAAAGUAGAGAAAUCUUGAUUCAGAAUGUAUAAUUUCCUUUAUAUCAGAAGGUUUAAAUAGCUAAUAUAAACAAUGAAGAGUCAUGCUGAAGAUAAGUUCUGUUAUAUCAUACCGCACAUUCUCCUUUGGCUAUCAGAGACUUUACACUGGAGAGAAAAAUGUGAGAGUGUUUAACUGGACAGCCCAGAGACCUGGUAUGUAGUCCUAAUCUGCCACUGCCUUGGACAACUUGCCUACUUCCACCAGGUUAUGGUUCUUUAUUUGGUAAAUGAAUGAUUUUGGAGUUAGAAAUCUUGUAGGAGCUCUGUUAGCUCUAAAAUGCUACAACUCUAUAAAUAUAAUGAAUGCUGGGAAA